AGAUUUUGGGAAACUCACCUCUUAACAGAAGCCCACCCUCCAUCCCUGACACCAUGACCCACUGUUGCUCCCCUUGCUGUCAGCCUACCUGCUGCAGGACCACCUGCUGGCAGCCCACCACUGUGACCACCUGCAGCAGCACACCCUGCUGUCAGCCCUCCUGCUGUGUUUCCAGCUGCUGCCAGCCUUGCUGCCACCCAACUUGCUGUCAAAACACCUGCUGUAGGACCACCUGCUGCCAGCCCAUCUGUGUGACCAGCUGCUGCCAGCCUUCCUGCUGUAGCACACCCUGCUGCCAGCCCACAUGCUGUGGGUCCAGCUGUGGUCAGAGCAGCUCCUGUGCACCUGUGUACUGCAGAAGAACCUGCUACCACCCCACAAGUGUUUGUCUGCCUGGUUGCCUAAACCAGAGCUGUGGCUCCAACUGCUGCCAGCCCUGCUGCCGCCCAGCCUGCUGUGAGACCACCUGCUGCAGGACCACUUGUUUCCAGCCCACCUGUGUGUACAGCUGCUGCCAGCCUUCUUGCUGCUAAUCAACUCCCAAGAGAACUACCAUCCUCACACAACAACCUUCAGCUCAACUGACUUGUCUUUUGAGGGACUAAUUUACUUUGCUGCUGACAGCCACCAUGCUCUCACCCAAAUUUUUAUGAAUUCUCUACAUGUUUAAAAUCUUGGGAAUCUGCUUGAGGGAGGGCAGAAUACUUCAUCCUCAUUCCCUCUUUCCUUACACCUUGUGGAUCAUGUGCCAGCUUCGUCUGUUCUUAAUUUGGAGUCAUGAUCUCAGCUUUGUCUCAAAAAUCAAGAGCUUCAUUCUUUGCUUCUAAGGAAUUUAGGUUUCUGCAACUGAUCAAUCAUCUUUGCAAUUAUAUUUUCAUUUUAAAUAUCCUUCUCAUGGUUCUUGUAUCCUUCUUUCUUCUUUUCACGAUAACUUUGGGUUAUGUCUCUGGUAGCAGAGAUUCUUACCUAUAUGUUUCUGAAUAAACUCUGAACCAUCUUCAUCUCA